AUGCAACCUGGGAGGGCUCGGGGACGGGAAACCCACUCUCAGCCCGCUCCACUUCGCCGAAGAAUUCCAAACCACCCCAGGCUCAGCAGUGUGGAUUGCUCCGCCCAGAGACCGUGGAGGAGGCAGCAGAGAGGUCACAGAGCACAGCAGGCGGGAGAAAACCGCCUCCCGCGAGGUCCAACAGAAACCACGGAGCUCCGGACACUCGGGAUCCCGGGCCGCGGGCGCGCGGCCAGAGCGGCGGGGUGCGAGCGCGGGGGUGCGGACUCACCUCGCGCUUGGGGUGGCCGGGAGCGCGCGCCGCCUCAGUUCCGCGGCUUCCGGCCACAGAGUCCCCGCGCAAAGCGCCGCCGCGUAGCGGGAGGGGCGACCGCGGCAGGAGCUCGGGUUCUUCCUAACCCGAGCCCGCCGCGCUGGCUCCGCCGAGGACGCCAGCAGCUGCAGGCAGCGCUUCAGCUCUCGCCGCCUCGCCAUCGUUGGGGCGAGUCGUCGCCGGGUCACUCCCUUAUUAUGACCUUCGAAUCUGACAGCAGGGCCAGCGGUGGCCUCCUUCAGGCUGCCUCUCCAGCCCUUACCAAGAUGGCCGCCCCUGUGGGCCGGGGCGCCGAAGCCAUCUUGGUAAAGGAAGCGCCUGGGAGCACGCGGCCUGCCCCGGCCCGCCUCGCGACUCAAACACUCUGCGGGGACCCUCCUAAGAUCAAAUUGGUUCCCCCCGCUGUCCUAAGCCAGAGGCUUACUUUCAGAUCGCAUGAACGCAUUCCUGGACACCAGCCACAGUUGCUAAAACUAAAUGGGAUCCUGCAGACCCAUUGACGGACUGUCAUAGCCAACUCAAUCACAGUCGAGAAGCAUUUGAAUACUUACAGCCUAUGGCGCUAGGAUCCUGGUAGCGAAGAAACUAAACUCUAAUUUGAAAUGUUGUACAGCUAGCUUAGAGUGGCUGCUGAACUUAAGGGUGAUUAAGAGCUGCUUGCACGUGGGUGGAGCUGAAACUGCAUAAGGUGAAUAAUACCUUUGUGCAACAGAAGAAAAAAAAAAGUAACAGCAUACAUACAAACCCAAAGGAAUUAGAGGAGACAGCACUGAUUGCAGUGACAGAAGCGGUGCCAGCUAACUCCCCACCAUCAAAAGUAUCUUCUGCUGUAGCCUGGCACAAGUUUCAAGCAUCCACUGGGGGUCUUGGGAUGUGUCGCCCUGCAGAUAAGGGCAACUGCUGUGCAGCAUGAACAGUAUGGAGACAAUACUUAUCUUCAUGGAGUUUAUAUUAGAGUAAGACAAGAGGUAGGAGACUGCCUAUUUUAUUGUUCUCUUGAAAAGACUGGGUAUUUUACUUUUAUGAAAGGCUUUAUAGCCUGCAGGGGCAUUCUAAUAUGGAUUUUGGGGGUGAAGAGACAAAUAGGUGUGGAAAGUAAGUUCAGGGGUUCAGAGACCCAUAGGUUUUUUAAAAGAGAAGUCAGGGGAAGGUCUCUUAAGGUAGUAGUGGAGUCCAAAUUAUUCUAUGUCCCUUGUAGCUCCUACCCUUUGUAUGCAGUAGUUUUUUUUUUAAAUCGAAGACGGGGGAAGGUCUCUUAAGGUAAUAGUAGAGACCAAAUUAUUCU